AGUGGGAGCUGCGACCGCGCUCCCUGUGAGGUGGGCAAGCGGCGAAAUGGCGCCCUCCGGGAGUCUUGCAGUUCCCCUGGCAGUCCUGGUGCUGUUGCUUUGGGGUGCUCCCUGGACGCACGGGCGGCGGAGCAACGUUCGCGUCAUCACGGACGAGAACUGGAGAGAACUGCUGGAAGGAGACUGGAUGAUAGAAUUUUAUGCCCCGUGGUGCCCUGCUUGUCAAAAUCUUCAACCGGAAUGGGAAAGUUUUGCUGAAUGGGGAGAAGAUCUUGAGGUUAAUAUUGCGAAAGUAGAUGUCACAGAGCAGCCAGGACUGAGUGGACGGUUUAUCAUAACUGCUCUUCCUACUAUUUAUCAUUGUAAAGAUGGUGAAUUUAGGCGCUAUCAGGGUCCAAGGACUAAGAAGGACUUCAUAAACUUUAUAAGUGAUAAAGAGUGGAAGAGUAUUGAGCCCGUUUCAUCAUGGUUUGGUCCAGGUUCUGUUCUGAUGAGUAGUAUGUCAGCACUCUUUCAGCUAUCUAUGUGGAUCAGGACUUGCCAUAACUACUUUAUUGAAGACCUUGGAUUGCCAGUGUGGGGAUCAUAUACUGUUUUUGCUUUAGCAACUCUGUUUUCCGGACUGUUAUUAGGACUCUGUAUGAUAUUUGUGGCAGAUUGCCUUUGUCCUUCAAAAAGGCGCAGACCACAGCCGUACCCAUACCCUUCAAAAAAAUUAUUAUCAGAAUCUGCACAACCUUUGAAAAAAGUGGAGGAGGAACAAGAGGCGGAUGAAGAAGAUGUUUCAGAAGAAGAAGCUGAAAGUAAAGAAGGAACAAACAAAGACUUUCCACAGAAUGCCAUAAGACAACGCUCUCUGGGUCCAUCAUUGGCCACAGAUAAAUCCUAGUUAAAUUUUAUAGUUAUCUUAAUAUUAUGAUUUUGAUAAAAACAGAAGAUUGAUCAUUUUGUUUGGUUUGAAGUGAACUGUGACUUUUUUGAAUAUUGCAGGGUUCAGUCUAGAUUGUCAUUAAAUUGAAGAGUCUACAUUCAGAACAUAAAAGCACUAGGUAUACAAGUUUGAAAUAUGAUUUAAGCACAGUAUGAUGGUUUAAAUAGUUCUCUAAUUUUUGAAAAAUCGUGCCAAGCAAUAAGAUUUAUGUAUAUUUGUUUAAUAAUAACCUAUUUCAAGUCUGAGUUUUGAAAAUUUACAUUUCCCAAGUAUUGCAUUAUUGAGGUAUUUAAGAAGAUUAUUUUAGAGAAAAAUAUUUCUCAUUUGAUAUAAUUUUUCUCUGUUUCACUGUGUGAAAAAAAGAAGAUAUUUCCCAUAAAUGGGAAGUUUGCCCAUUGUCUCAAGAAAUGUGUAUUUCAGUGACAAUUUCGUGGUCUUUUUAGAGGUAUAUUCCAAAAUUUCCUUGUAUUUUUAGGUUAUGCAACUAAUAAAAACUACCUUACAUUAAUUAAUUACAGUUUUCUACACAUGGUAAUACAGGAUAUGCUACUGAUUUAGGAAGUUUUUAAGUUCAUGGUAUUCUCUUGAUUCCAACAAAGUUUGAUUUUCUCUUGUAUUUUUCUUACUUACUAUGGGUUACAUUUUUUAUUUUUCAAAUUGGAUGAUAAUUUCUUGGAAACAUUUUUUAUGUUUUAGUAAACAGUAUUUUUUUGUUGUUUCAAACUGAAGUUUACUGAGAGAUCCAUCAAAUUGAACAAUCUGUUGUAAUUUAAAAUUUUGGCCACUUUUUUCAGAUUUUACAUCAUUCUUGCUGAACUUCAACUUGAAAUUGUUUUUUUUUUUUUUUCUUUUUGGAUGUGAAGGUGAACAUUCCUGAUUUUUGUCUGAUGUGAAAAAGCCUUGGUAUUUUACAUUUUGAAAAUUCAAAGAAGCUUAAUAUAAAAGUUUGCAUUCUACUCAGGAAAAAGCAUCUUCUUGUAUAUGUCUUAAAUGUAUUUUUGUCCUCAUAUACAGAAAGUUCUUAAUUGAUUUUACAGUCUGUAAUGCUUGAUGUUUUAAAAUAAUAACAUUUUUAUAUUUUUUAAAAGACAAACUUCAUAUUAUCCUGUGUUCUUUCCUGACUGGUAAUAUUGUGUGGGAUUUCACAGGUAAAAGUCAGUAGGAUGGAACAUUUUAGUGUAUUUUUACUCCUUAAAGAGCUAGAAUACAUAGUUUUCACCUUAAAAGAAGGGGGAAAAUCAUAAAUACAAUGAAUCAACUGACCAUUACGUAGUAGACAAUUUCUGUAAUGUCCCCUUCUUUCUAGGCUCUGUUGCUGUGUGAAUCCAUUAGAUUUACAGUAUCGUAAUAUACAAGUUUUCUUUAAAGCCCUCUCCUUUAGAAUUUAAAAUAUUGUACCAUUGAAGAGUUUGGAUGUGUAACUUGUGAUGCCUUAGAAAAAUAUCCUAAGCACAAAAUAAACCUUUCUAACCACUUCAUUAAAGCUGAAGACCAGUAUGAUUUCUGGUUGCUUUUUGAAGGUAUGCUUUAUUACUUUGUAUUUAACGAUGUUCAGAUGAGUAGUUGUGUGUUCCUAUAUAUGUACUUGAUAUGUGUAAUCAAAAGACUGCCUUCUUUUUCUAUUGAGAUGUUUAAGGACAGUAAUGCUCAUUAAUCAAGCAUUUUUUUUUUUUAGUGUUCUAGUAUAUGUGACAUGGCCAAUUUUUUUAUUAGAAAAUAUGUGACCAGAAAGAUUCUAUAGAGUAAAAAAUCAAAGCAAAACAAAAACCACAAAAAGACCCCUGUACUAUAGAAAAUGUAAAGUUGGCUGAACAGAUAGGGUCUUGAAAUUUCAGGAAACAUAUAAUCUCACGGUUCUUAAAGAUUGUCACUGUAGACAUCUGAGUAAUUAAUUUUCAGUUAGUAACAGGCUUAUAGAAACUUUGGGAUUAUUUACAAAUGGUUUAGGAAAGAAUAAGGUAUAGUAAAAGUAAUAUCCUGGAGAAUUCUGGGCCACCUACCCACCAUAAUCAAUUCAGCUGUACUACUGAAGUAUUGUAAAAUCUGAUCUCUAGAGGAAAAUACAGUAUUCUACCUUACGUUGUGUAAAUACUUAAUGAUUAUCAGAAAGACUGAAAAAAGUUUUAAUGAAGAAUUCUGGCUACAUCUAACAGCUGCCAUUUACCAAGUACCUACUGGAGCUUUGUUGUUUUCUUGUAUUUAUUAAUUUAGUCCUAAUGACAACUGCAAGACAGGUAAGCAUUGCACAUCUUUCAGGUGAGUCAGCCCAGAGGUGUGGUACAAAUAGGUAAAAUUUGAAUCUAAUUCUUGUUCCAAAUCUUUUUUUGUUUGUUUUUGUUUUUGUUUUUUUUCUUCAGUGUGGGUACAUGAAAUUCAGCAAUCUCUUAUUUUGGUCUUUUUUUUUUUUUUGAGACAGAGUUUCACUCUUGUUGCCCAGGCUGGAGUGCAAUGGCAUGAUCUUGGCUCACUGCAACCUCCACCUCCUGGGUUCAAGCAGUUCUUCUGCCUCAGCCUCCCAAGUAGCUGGGAUUACAGGCAUGUGCCACCAUGCCCGGCUAUUAUUUUGGUCUUAAAAUUUCACUCCUGUCAGAAUGUAGGAGUGAAUAAAUGCUAUUCAUAAAUAACCAUAAUUAUUCAGUAUUUGCAGUCUCGUGAUGUUGGUUAUUGCAUAAAGUAAGUUAUUGCAGUAAAUGAUGCUUUAGAAAGCAAUUUUCUCUCAUCAGUUUCGUCCUUAUUCAGCCUUACACAAAAAAAGGCAUAGUUCUGGGCUUAAUUGUGAUGUAAUUAAAAUUAUUGAGUGAACAUUUUGGCUCAUAUUUUAUGACAUUGUAGUUCAUCCCCAUGGUCAAUUUAAGGUAGAGUUCUUACAAUAUAUUACUUUCAAUAUAGGUAUUUUAUUAAUAAGAAUUUAUUUCAGUUGGACUUAUUAAAUGAGUGGUUUUGCUGAGUGUAUGAGUCUAUAAAUAAAAUUUUAAUUGAACAUCAUUGGAGAUUUAGAUAUGUUGGUACUGCUUAUCUAGCAACUUUUGUAUUUGUGAAACCAUUAAAACUAGAGUAACAAUAAAUUUAAGUUGGAAUUUUGGUAAUAUGUAAA